ACUUCCUUUUCAGAGCUGUAUCCGGGUCGCUGCUUUCCCUAUUGUCUGAGGCAGCCGCCCUCGCGCUGUGCAAUUUCUGGUCUUUCGUUGCUUCUGGUCCAGGCUAAUAAAGUUUUUCUUUCUUUAAUUUUUUUUCUUCUAGUUUUAACGGGAGAAAUUAACUCCCCGGGGCCGCCGGGUUGACUGCGCUGCCUGGGCCGGAGGUCUUCUCCGGCCAGGGAGCGCUGUGGGAAGGGGCUCGAGCGGCCAGGGCCAGGCGAGGCCGGGGGGGCGGGGGGUUAGGGGACCGCGGGGCUACUCUUGGGAGCGCCCCUGUCCGGCUGGCUGCGCGCCGGUUUUAAAUAGCAUCUUUCGGACUUGUCUUCGCGGCCCCAGUCCCCGACCUCGGCGCUGCCUGGGCUCCUGCAGCCUCUCCCUAAGUCUUCUCCAAACGACCACCUCACGGAUUCCUUAUGGAUCGCAGCUCCAAGAGGAGGCAGGUGAAGCCUUUGGCAGCUUCUCUGCUGGAAGCUCUUGAUUAUGAUAGUUCAGAUGACAGUGAUUUUAAAGUUGGAGAUGCCUCAGAUUCUGAAGGGAGUGGUAAUGGAAGUGAAGAUGCUUCAAAGGACAGUGGAGAAGGUUCCUGUAGUGAUUCUGAAGAAAAUAUUUUAGAAGAAGAACUGAAUGAAGAUAUUAAAGUAAAAGAAGAACAACUUAAAAAUUCUGCAGAGGAAGAAGUACUAUCAUCAGAAAAACAAUUAAUUAAAAUGGAAAAGAAGGAAGAAGAAGAAAAUGGAGAAAGACCUAGAAAGAAAAAGGAGAAAGAGAAGGAAAAAGAAAAGGAAAAGGAGAAAGAGAAGGAAAGAGAGAAGGAAAAAGAAAAAGCAACAGUAUCUGAGAAUGUGGCUGCUUCUGCUGCUGCCACCACACCAGCCACAAGUCCUCCUGCUGUUAACACAUCCCCUUCUGUUCCCACUACGACAACCGCUACAGAGGAACAAGUCAGCGAGCCAAAAAAAUGGAACCUUCGACGAAACCGACCACUUCUGGAUUUUGUGUCCAUGGAAGAGCUGAAUGACAUGGAUGACUAUGACAGUGAGGAUGACAAUGAUUGGCGACCUACUGUAGUAAAGAGAAAAGGGAGAUCUGCGUCUCAGAAAGAGGGAAGUGAUGGAGACAAUGAGGAUGAUGAAGAUGAGGGAAGCGGGAGUGAUGAAGACGAGAAUGAUGAAGGCAAUGAUGAAGAUCAUAGUAGCCCUGCCAGUGAAGGGGGUUGCAAGAAGAAGAAGAGUAAAGUUCUUAGCAGAAACAGUGCUGAUGAUGAGGAACUGACCAAUGAUAGCCUGACCCUAUCUCAAAGCAAGAGUAAUGAGGACUCGCUGAUUCUUGAGAAGAGUCAAAACUGGAGCUCUCAAAAAAUGGACCAUAUUCUGAUUUGCUGUGUUUGUCUGGGAGAUAAUAGUGAGGACGCUGAUGAAAUAAUUCAGUGUGACAAUUGUGGCAUUACAGUCCAUGAAGGUUGUUAUGGAGUUGAUGGAGAGAGUGACUCUAUUAUGAGUUCAGCUUCUGAAAACUCCACUGAACCUUGGUUUUGUGAUGCCUGUAAAUGUGGUGUUUCUCCUAGCUGUGAACUGUGUCCUAAUCAGGAUGGAAUUUUCAAGGAGACAGAUGCUGGAAGAUGGGUUCAUAUUGUUUGUGCCCUGUAUGUUCCUGGAGUAGCCUUUGGAGAUAUUGACAAAUUACGACCAGUAACACUAACGGAAAUGAACUAUUCCAAAUAUGGUGCCAAGGAGUGUAGCUUUUGUGAAGACCCUCGCUUUGCUAGAACUGGGGUUUGCAUUAGCUGUGAUGCAGGGAUGUGCAGAGCCUAUUUCCAUGUGACCUGUGCUCAAAAGGAAGGUCUGCUUUCAGAGGCAGCGGCGGAAGAGGAUAUAGCAGAUCCAUUCUUUGCUUAUUGUAAGCAACAUGCAGAUAGGUUAGACAGAAAGUGGAAGAGAAAAAACUACUUGGCUCUACAGUCCUAUUGUAAAAUGUCUUUGCAAGAGAGAGAGAAGCAACUAUCACCAGAAGCACAGGCAAGGAUCAAUGCCCGGCUUCAGCAGUAUCGUGCCAAAGCAGAACUAGCUCGAUCUACCAGACCCCAGGCCUGGGUUCCAAGGGAAAAAUUGCCCAGACCACUCACCAGCAGUGCUUCAGCUAUUCGUAAACUUAUGCGGAAAGCAGAACUCAUGGGGAUCAGUACAGAUAUCUUUCCAGUGGACAAUUCAGAUACUAGUUCUAGUGUGGAUGGAAGGAGAAAACAUAAGCAACCAGCUCUCACUGCAGAUUUUGUGAAUUAUUAUUUUGAGAGAAAUAUGCGCAUGAUUCAAAUUCAGGAAAAUAUGGCUGAACAAAAGAAUAUAAAAGAUAAAUUAGAGAAUGAACAAGAAAAGCUUCAUGUAGAAUAUAAUAAGCUAUGUGAAUCUUUAGAAGAACUACAAAACCUGAAUGGAAAACUUCGAAGUGAAGGACAAGGAAUAUGGGCUUUACUAGGCAGAAUCACAGGGCAGAAGUUGAAUAUACCGGCAAUUUUGCGAGCACCCAAGGAGAGAAAACCAAGUAAAAAAGAAGGAGGCACACAAAAGACAUCUACUCUUCCUGCAGUACUUUAUAGUUGUGGGAUUUGUAAGAAGAACCAUGAUCAGCAUCUUCUUUUAUUGUGUGAUACCUGUAAACUACAUUACCAUCUUGGAUGUCUGGAUCCUCCUCUUACAAGGAUGCCAAGAAAGACCAAAAACAGUUAUUGGCAGUGCUCGGAAUGUGACCAGGCAGGGAGCAGUGACAUGGAAGCAGAUAUGGCCAUGGAAACCCUACCAGAUGGAACCAAACGAUCAAGGAGGCAGAUUAAGGAACCAGUGAAAUUUGUUCCACAGGAUGUGCCACCAGAACCCAAGAAGAUUCCGAUAAGAAACACGAGAACCAGAGGACGAAAACGAAGCUUCGUUCCUGAGGAAGAAAAACAUGAGGAAAGAGUUCCUAGAGAGAGAAGACAAAGACAGUCUGUGUUGCAAAAGAAGCCCAAGGCUGAAGAUUUAAGAACUGAAUGUGCAACUUGCAAGGGAACUGGAGACAAUGAAAAUCUUGUCAGAUACCCUUCAUGAGACCCAACUCUGCCACAGCUCAUCCUCGGAGGCAAUCCCGGAAACCUCUUUUAUAAGUGUGAUUUUAAAAAUGUGGAUUAAACUCUCGAUAGAGUACAUAAAGUAAAGGAGAACAGCUAUAUUGUCCUUUCUAUAAGCUUGUCACUGCAAAAAGUUGCCUUUUGCUUGUCAGGUUUGGAUAGAAUAUAAUUGAUUGGUUUGUUACUUGGACUAACAAGGCAGUAGAUUUGCCUGUGUGGAAUUUUUUUUCCUAUUUUUCUUCUUUUUGCUUUUUUUGCACUUAUCAGAAAUAUUUGAUGUGUGCAUUGUUGAAAAAUACUGGAUACAUGUCUUGUCAGAAUUGUCGUAUUAAGUAAUGUCUUUCCCUCUUGCUUCUUUGGCAAAUGUUGAUACACAGUGUUUGGACUUACUGAAGAGUUACUGAAGCCUGUGGGACUUAAUAAAUACAAUAUGCUACUCCCUGUUGUGAUUGAACAAUACAAAUAACAAACAAGAAAGACAAUGCAUUCCAUUAGUCUGCUAUUCUGUUUCCUUCAACUUCAUACAUAGAUUCAUAUAUGAAGUACUGCAUUGUAAAACAACUAUAGACUCAUAUUAAAUGUUAUUUCUAUUUAUAAUAUUCAGCAAAAGUGAAAGACUUGUGAAGCAUAUGACAUUCUAUUUUUGACUUAUUAGUCCUAGUGUGAAAGCAUUAAUAUUAUUAGCAUGAAAUUUUUACUUCAGAUUUUAAGCUCAUGAAUAAAGAUAUAUCUGUGUUGAUCUCUAGAUAUUUUUAGUAAUACCCAAAUAUAUUCAGUCCUUAUUGUUUUAAUAUAAGCUUUCUGUGUUCAGUAUAAUUUUAUUUUUCUCAACCUUAAAUAUGAACUUAGGAAAUAAGGAGGGAAGUACAAAGAUUAUUGACUAUACAACCUACCAGCUGAAAGAAAGAUCUUCAUCAACAUCUGUAUCUUUCCAGAGGUAUACAGAAUUAAAAUUUGAUCUUCAAGCUUUAAUGAUCCAGUUUUAAGUCAACGGCAGAAGUAUGUUGAAUAUUUCAUCACUCAAUCUUGAACUGAUUUAGAAGAGACUCUUUGCUGAAAUUGAAUUGCACUUAUACAUGUAAAUUGUCAACAUGUAAUUUGGAAUUUUCUGAUUAAUAAAUGUGGUUUUGGACAUCUUUUCGGGUAUAGUGACAAUGGAAAAUAGUUUAAACUUUAGGAAUAGAGUAGGUAAUGUUAUAGAUAAUCAAAAGCAAUUGUAAUUGUAAAGCUGCUGUAAUCUAGUGAUCUCUAGUUACAGUGAGGAACGCUAUGAUUGGAUGAGAUGUUUGAUAAAAGUAAAAUGUGUAUGAAAUUACAUAUAAACAGAUUAUUAGCUUAUUGAAAGAUCUCAUAACAUUGGAGGAAAAAUAUUCAUAAUCUUUAGCAAAACUAGUAGACUUUUGUUUAAAAGAAUAAGAUAGGACUAGUUGUCACUAUAUUAGCUUAAGGAAAUGUUGGUAAUUAUUACUGUUGCUGAACUCUGGCUGCUUUUAAGCAAAAUGACAGAUUGCCAUUUUCUAAGUGGAAUAUACUAAUCCAUUAGACCAUGGCCCUCUUUUAAUAUUUAGUGAGAAAUUACUCGCAGUUGCUUUAUUUUAGGUUUUUUGAGAAACUCUUAGGCCUUGUUUUGGUAUCACUGUUAAUCAAAAUCCUUUUCACUUUGAUUCCAAUUAUAAUACUAUAUUAUCAUCAUUUUCCAUCUUGCAUUUUCAGUGGUGGUGGAUAUUCUAUUCCACAUUUGGUGCUAGUCCUAAGAAUCUUUGUCACAUGUUAUACAUAUAGACUGCAAAAUUCAUAAGAUAUAGGUCCUGCAAAAAGUAUAGUUGAAGUAAGAAAACUUGAAGUAACUAGAAUAGAAUACUUUCUCCUAAUAAUCUCUUAAAUGCUCUCAUAUCCACAGUAUAAAAUUAUUCCGUGUCCAUAAUCGGUCCAACUACUAUAAGGAGAAAAUUGAUGUGUGCUUAAGAAAAUAUGUACUAAAUGAUUCAUAUUUCACAGACCUACAUAAGAAAAAAAUGGCACAUCAGGUAAAUGAUAGUUGUUUAUCACACAGUAGGGAAAGGAAGAAACAUGAAAAUAUCAGGAAGGAGAUGAAAUGUCUCUGAAAUACAGGAAGAAUGACAUAAUAGCAAGUAGUGGUUCUCAAACGUUGUGCAUUGGAAUCACAGGAAGGAUUUGUAAAAACACAGGUGACUACCCUAUUCCUCUCCUGGAUCUGCCCUCUGCCCACUUUACUCCCUCCCCCUUCACCCUGGAGUUUCUGAUUUAGUAGAAAAUUUGCAUUUCUAACAAGUUCCCAGCUGAUGCUGAUGCUACUGGCCUGGAACACCACAUUAAGAACCAUUCAUAGGUAGUAUUUUUUUUAAAACAUCGUUGUGUUGUGCUUAACAUUGAUUGAUAAAGGAAUGUGCUUUUAACAUCUCCUUAAAAGGUCCCUUAGAUUUCCUCUAGAUAAAAGAAUUAGUAAUUUCAUCUGCAACACAUACAAUUUUUUUUAAUUUUAUAAAAUUUAGUUAAAUGUUUGUUUUACACUGACUAUGGAAACAGCACUAUUUUAGAUACAGAAAGAAAUCAAUAAACAUAGCCUGUGUUCACAAUUCACUCAUCCUUUUGUUAUAAAAAGACUUGAAAUUAGGGUUAUGUUUUAACAUGAAAACAAAAUUUAGCCUUAGCUUUUAUCCAUCUUAACUUUAGAAAUUAUAUUUAUGCAUUGUUUAUAGAUCAUUGUCAUUCGUUGUUGCUUAAGUGUUCAUCUGAUUUUAUAUUUAUGAUGUUAAAAAUAGACUGCUGACCAAUAAAUAAUAAAAUAUUUACACUCCAUUCUAUUUCCCUGUAUUCACAUCCUAUUAAUGAAAACCACUGGUUUUAAACAAAGUUACUUAUUUCAUAAAACUCACCACUAUUUUACUUGAUUCUCAAUAUGAGAAUAUUUCAUGACUAUUUCACCAAAAUUUAUUCAAGGAAUUCAGAAGGACUCUCCAGCAGAGCAGAAUAUUUACAUCAUUAAAUUUUUAAAAAAAUUUAAAAAUGGCAAUUGAAACUUGUUUAAGAGACUCAACUUGGAGUUUCCUGACAUACGAAGGCAGAAUCAUUUUUUCUACCUGUCUGAAUCAGCACUUUGUAAGUUUACAUAAAAUUAAGGAUUGUGAUUUCUAAGAUAGGCAUGCUUUGCAAAUAUUUCUCUAUAAAAGUGGAAGCCUCUUUCCCAUAGUGCUCACUUUAAGGCUUUCUGUAGGCCUGCCGAUAAGAUUCACUGCUGUUCAGGUACAUAAGAUGUAAUGUAAUUGGAUGCACAUGCUGGGCUUUGUAAAUAAAAUGAGAUUGACACCCAGCAAUUAUCUCAUUUAUCUGAUUUACAUUGUAAAAUCAGGAUCUACACUAUUGAUUAGAGCAUAAUUAGUUAAUUAUGAACAGGGAAAUACAAAGUUACAUGGAGCUUGAGCUCAGCAGGUUGUACUGCUGAAAAAUUUCCAAGGGCAUGAGCAGAUGGAAAUCAGUUUAUUAAAGAACAAAGCAGACAUGUUUCAGGUAUGGAAAUGUCUAAUUCUUCUCUCAUGCUGUGAAGAGUUGCUUGACCUUAUUGUGUAUUUUUAUAUGAAUUGUUUUGUCUCAUCUUUCAUUUUCUUGUUUCACAUUUAAUCUUGUAAUCUGGCUGCCACAGAUAUAGCUAACUGAAUUGAUCCCACUCUUUAAGUGACUAUUAAAUACAGAUUUGGAUUUGGAUAUUUUUCUAAUUUUUUAAAAUUAAUUUUUAUGUGUAAAGAAUAUUUUUGUCUUUCUUACUACCCAUUCAUUCAUUAUUGGCUGAUACAGAAGUCUGUAGUGGUAUUAAUGAAAUAGGUUCAAGCCCUCCACGUUAGUCUUAUAUUUGUGAAAUGAUUAAAAACCAUUUUCUAAUUAUUUUGUAUAGAAACUGCUCAUGUAGGUAAUUUGCACUAAAAUUGUUGUAAAUUACAAGGAAUAAAAUAUUGUACUUAUUGAUACUAAAUGUUAUUCCGUAUUGGUAGAAUGCAGAAUUUUGUGCAAGCUUGUAUUAUUUGUAAAGUGAUUUAACUCAUUGACCACAAUUUGUAUUUUCUCCAUCUGUUAAGAUGUUUAAUCAAAAUAAUUGGCCACUAUUCAAUGAAAGAACUCAUCGCUACCUGUUAAUAGAUUUGCGUAGAUGUUUGAGCUGCUAGUGAGAUUUUUAUUUAAGUAAUGACAGUAUUCAAGACUAAUUUUUUUGAACAUUCUUGUGAUGGAAUUUUUACACAGAAAUGAAAAAGUUGGAAAAUCCAACCCAUCAGUUCUCUGGAUAUUUAGUUUUUUUUAAGUGGACAGACAUAAUAGUCUAUAUUUUCAGAGUCCAGUUUUUGUUUUGCUUUAUAUAAACUUAUAGGGGCUACAAGUAAAAUGUUCCAUUGGCAUAAAAGAUAAUGUGAUUAUCACAAUCAACUUGAUCAUAAAAAUGUACAUCCUUGUUCAAGUCUAUGUUAUGGAUUUUGCUUCUUUCUAAAGUUUAGCUUACAAAUGGCUAUAAAUUAUUUGCAUAGGAGGUGCACUUAAUUGUUUCAGUUAGGUUUUAAAAAGUAGUUGUAGUUUACUCCUCUAAUGAAAUUAGAGAUGUUAAACCCUUUGGAAUACUGACUUUUGGCCUCUUAGGCAUUCGAUGAAAUAAAUCAGCUGCUUCUUUUUACUUGUUUGCAUAUUCUCAAUAGUCAGGUAAACACCUGACUAAUUGCUUGUUAUAUGGAUCAUAGCACAUAUGAAGGUAAAUCAUUUUUUUCCCUCUUCUUUGUUUAGGGUGCUAUUCUUAAUCAUAUACUAAGUAAGUAUUUUACAUACAUAUAGACUGUGUUUAUUUGGUCACUACAUUUUGUUAAUGGGUAAAAGACCAUAUAUUAAGCUACUUUGUUAUUUACAUCUAUAUCUGUUAUUAAUCUGAUAGCUAGGAAGUUGUAUUUAGUAAGAAUCUAAUUAGGUUUGCUUUUAUCUUAUAAUUGGGAUUCCUUUAUGCUCUAUAGUGUUAAUGUGUACAGUGUUUAUUAGAGGCUUAAAUGAUACUUCUUUAAGCAUCCAGUUUUUAUUUUAUUAAAAAAUCUUAGUGUUUCUUUACAGGUUAGUUUUGUAUUCUUUUUUAAUAUUUUAAGACAUUGCCUUCCUAUUUAAUAAUGUGCUAUUCGUAUAAUAAUCUGUUUUUAUUACAUAGACAUUUGUGUUAUUUAAUAAAGUAUAUUGUGUUAUAUCCCUAUACUUUUGUGGGUCAAUGACUGCUUCUGAAAAAGUUUUUUAAAACAUUUUAUUCACUAUUUAUUUUGAUAAAUUUUGUCCUAUAUUAUGUGCUGCAUGUGUUUCCAAGUUUAUGUAAGAAAUAAAGGUAGAAACCAUAAAUAGGUCAAUAACUACUUUAACUCCAUUGCAGCUUUUAGGUAGCAGAUGAUUAUAGUCCCUUACGAGUUUUUUUAAAUGGUCUAAAUUUGCAACAUAGCUCAGGGUUUGUUGGGUGACAGGAUUUGAUGAAGAUUACAAAGUGGUAUUUGUGUGUAAAAUUAAUAAGCCACUAUUUUGGCCAUCCACAUUGUUCUUUGAUUUCUUGGGUUCUUAAUGGUAUCUCUUAUAUUUGUCCACAGUUUAUUAAUUCUUGCAAGUUCUGCUAGAGUUCACUUGUGUCCAGUAAGAUGUUUCUGUGAUUAGCACAUAGAGCUAUGGAUUUUUUCAAUUCAAUAUUCUAAGAUAGAAACAACAGAUUUUUUUCACAUUGAAAUAAUUUUGGGACAUCUUUACAAAGAUCUUAUAUUUGUAUAUUUGUUUAUCACCAAAACUAUUGACUUCAAGAUUGGAUUCUUUUCUUUUUUUCCCCUUCUGUUUUUUGGAUUUUGGCAGUUCCUAAGGGUACUACUACUUUUUGCUACUUAGUCUUGAAGCUGAAGCUUUUAUUUACUUUUGAGUGAGCUAGAACCUCAGAGAACUUGCCUAUCACCCCUAAUUCUGACAAGCAAAUUCUUUUUCCUUUGGAAUGCAUCACAAAUACAUGAGAGUUCCACAUGUCGACUAAGUAAUUCUGAAAGGUAUCACUAAUGAAGGAAUCAAUCAGCAAGGAUUAGGUCAUUUUUAAAUGGCAUGUAUUUGUUAUCUUCUGAUAAGCUAGCAUAUAAAAUCUUUCUCUUCCUCUUUUCAUUAGUUCUUGAGCUGAAAGAUAAUUUAAUUGUACGAGUAGUUGAAAUCAGCAACAGAUUGGAACUGUGUUAGUGUAGCAAACUUGUUCUUGGUUUAUUAGCUGGAAUUUCAUAGCUAUAUCAACAAGAAUUAUUUAUGUACAUUAAGGUGAUAAAUAAUGAAUUAUGAUACACAUGCAUCAUGAUAGUUGCCUCAAGUUAUACACUAGAAAUCAUAAUUUGAAAAUUAUUAUGACACAGAGUUAUAAAGUAAAUAUGCAGUAAUUAGGUAGUAAAUUGAUGUGAACUAGGAAAAUGUUAAUACUUCAUCAAGAACUUUGAUUAUUAGCAAUCUGAACUCUGGCGCACUACCCAAAAACCUAAAGUUAAGGAGAAAAGACUAUAGUUAACAAACAAAAUUGAGCCCAUUUACUUAACUCAGUAGCAAUUAUCAUUUUCAUGUAUUUUUACUGUCAGUUUACAUAGCCUCAGUAAGUUUUAGUGGUCUGGUUUCUGAAUCCAUAACAGAUUGUUGUUGGGGAAUUUAUGCUUAAGCAAACACACCGAAAAUAUCAGGAAGCAGUGGCUGAUAGUUUUCAGGCAAGUGAGGACCCUGAAAAUCUACAAAAAUUGAAUACAAGAAUUCAAAUAGAACAGCUGACUCCUGGUCCUCAUUCCAAGGACAAAAGGCUGACACACUGCUAGACCUGUAGCAGCAUAUGUUAUUCUUACUGAUGACCUGAGAUGACAAAUAUAAAUUAUAUUUAAUAUGUUUAUUUGAUGAAACGAGCAAUGUGAUUUUUAAAUUUCGCAUCAAAGAUGAUUAAAACUCCAGUUUUUAUGUAUGAAGGAGUAUGCUCUCAGUUAUUUAGAAAUCUCAGCCUUCUCAUAAACUCAGAAAUACUUAUACUUUGAAGGUUUCUAUAUCCAUAGGUUUAAUCGAAAUUUUGGCUAAUGAAAGGUAAAUAUGUUGUACUGAGAAAGAGCAUAAAAUUAUGUGGGCUUGCCAGUCUCUUUAUGUCACAUUUGAACUUAGCUUAUAUUAUUUAUUAUUCUUUCUUAAUGCCAGAACAACAGGUAUUUGAACAUUUUAACUGCUUUUAAAUAUAUUUUUAGAUGUGUGAUAUUGUCAUAGUAAAUAAAGUACUGUUGGUCCUAUUGGUCCUAUUUGAUUUUAUCUAUUCCUGUAGCUAGAACUGUCAUAGUAAGCAUUUUUUAAAGUCUUGAAUCUACAAGGUUUUUGGAAAAGUACAUAAGCUUAUUUUAUUCAUAAGGAGAAAGUUGUAGAGGAAGAAAUGCAUAAACUUAGGACAUUCAUUUGUGUUUUAAACUUCUUUAUAUCUGAGUAACUUAAUUAAGUUGCUUAACUUUUCUGGAACUCUUGAUUCCCCAAAUGAGUUUUUGGAAGAUUGGACUUUUGUAUCAUAAUAUGAAAUUUCUACUAAAAAUGUAGAUUUACAGUCCCUUUUAUUAUGAUGGUUUCUUAAAGUCAAUUGUUUUUCUUUGUGUGUUGUUUAUGUAAGAAGAGCUUCUUCCCCCUUUUUUCCUAAAAGGUUAUUGAAUAGUAGUUUUUAACUUUAAUCAAGUAAUAUAUGUUCUAUAAAUUUUCCCCUUGGUUUCUUAAUUGCAGAUUUCUUGACAUUUGAAGUUUUAAAUCAGUGAAAGAUAA